AGUCACAACACGGUGGGGCUCCCUGGCUGCGCCCGGCCCGGCAGCUACGGGCCCAGCGCCUGGUGGCGGCGCUGAGGGGUCGCCGAGAGGGGCCCGGCGGCGUCUGCGGGGGCCGCUCCCUCGGUGGGCCGCGGGCGAGGCAUGAGCGCGGGCUCCCCCUGCCUCCGGAGCGCCGGCGGGGGACCGGGGGGCAGGAGAUGUGCCUGUCCUUAGCGGCCCAGGAAGCAGCAUGCACCCCGAUGCGACCGACAGUGGCGGCGCCGGCCCCAGCCCCGCGCGGGCCGCAGGCGCCGGCGGCCGUCCUGUCUCGGGCUUCAGGGGCGAGCGGCGGCCGGAGUCCCCGGGGGACGCGGAGGCAGCAGCAGCGGCGGCGCCGGGGGCCCCGGGCGGCCGGAGCUGGUGGAAGCCCGUGGCGGUGGCCGCACUCGCCGCCGUGGCCCUCUCCUUCCUGGGGCCCGGCAGCGGGGAGGCGGCGGGGGCCGCGGGGCUGAGCUCCGUCCUGUUCAGGCUCAGCCUGUACCUGAGCUGCGCGGCGGCCGCCUUCCUGCUGGGGAUCCUGUUUGCCCUCGUCUGCCGGAGCCCGCGCGCCCAGCCGCCCGACUUCGCCGCCGCCUGGAGCCGGCUGGCCGCGACCUCAGCCGCCCGCCGCCCGCCGGGGAGUCCUGUGUAUGGAAACUCACAUGAGUCAGCUCAGUCUAGAAGGGUAGUAAUUUCUCAUAAUAUGGAUAAAGCUCUGAAAGAAGUGUUCGACUACAGUUAUAGAGAUUACAUUCUGUCCUGGUAUGGAAACCUCAGCAGAGAUGAGGGACAACUUUACCAUCUGCUCUUGGAAGACUUUUGGGAAAUUGCCAGACAGCUGCACCACAGACUGAGUCACGUGGAUGUGGUUAAAGUUGUCUGCAAUGAUGUUGUGAGGACUUUACUCACUCAUUUCUGUGACCUGAAAGCUGCCAAUGCCAGACAUGAAGAACAGCCAAGACCUUUUGUGUUGCACGCAUGCUUGAGGAACUCAGAUGAUGAAGUAAGAUUUCUACAAACGUGUUCUCGGGUUCUGGUGUUUUGUCUCCUCCCCUCAAAGGAUGUGCAGUCUCUCAGCUUACGUAUAAUGCUUGCAGAAAUUCUCACAACAAAAGUCUUGAAGCCGGUAGUGGAGUUACUGAGUAAUCCAGAUUACAUUAACCAAAUGCUGCUUGCCCAGCUGGCGUACAGAGAGCAAAUGAAUGAGCAUCACAAGAGAGCCUACACCUAUGCCCCCUCUUACGAGGACUUCAUCAAGCUCAUUAACAGCAACUCUGAUGUGGAGUUCUUGAAGCAACUAAGGUAUCAAAUUGUAGUGGAAAUAAUCCAGGCGACUACAAUUAGCAGCUUUCCCCAACUGAAGAGGCACAAAGGUAAAGAAACUGCGGCAAUGAAAGCUGAUCUCCUGAGGGCCAGGAACAUGAAGAGGUACAUCAACCAACUGACUGUGGCAAAGAAGCAGUGUGAGAAGAGAAUCCGAAUCCUGGGAGGCCCUGCCUAUGACCAGCAAGAGGAUGGGGCCCUGGAUGAGGGGGAAGGGCCUCAAAGCCAGAAGAUGGAGUCUCACUCUGUCGCCCAGGCUGGCAUGCAUUGGCGCGAUAUCGGCUCACUGCAACCUCCACCUCCCGGGUUCAGGCCAUUCUCCUGCCUCAGCCUCCCGAGCAGCUGGGACUACAGACGCCCGCCACCACACCCAGCUAAAUUUUUUUUGUAUCUUUAGUAGAGACGCGGUUUCACUGUGUUAGGCAGGAUGGUCUCGAUAUCCUGACCUCAUGAUCUGCCCACCUCAGCAUUCCAGUGUGUUGGGAUUACAGGCGUGAGCCACUGCGCCUGGCCUUGAUUUGUUCUUUUCAGACAUUCAGGAAAAGAGAAACUCAUUUCUGUUGCAAUAAUUCAUCCUCAGAGUAAAACCAUUUCCUCUAAUCUUCAGGAUGGAAGGCUAAGAUAAGACAGAAUUCCAAUAGUUAUGGUCAUUUGCUAUUUGAAAGGUAAGACUUUGGUUAGUUUGGGGCCAUUCUGAUGUCUUCAUGAGUGGGAAGAAAACUUUUGCUAUGACCUAAUCAUAUGUGAUCCAGAAGAAUUACCAUUAACUUUAUUUCAGAAUUUAGACUUCCAAAUCAGGUUAAUCCUCCAAUUAAAAGAAAGAUUCAGAGUGAAUUUUUUAAAAGGCAAGGCAGUUAUAUGUUGCUUACAAGAAACUAAACAUAAAGGCACAGAUAAGUUGGAAGUAAGAGGGAAAAAGACAUGCGAAUACUAAGUAUAAGAGAUCUAGAGCAGCUACUGUGAAUAUCAGACAAAAUAGACUUCGGAACAGGAAGUAGAACCAGAGAUGAAGAACCUUUCAUUAUGAUAAAGGAGUCAGUUCGUCAGGAAGAUAGAAUAAUCAAAUGUUCUCAAUCAAUAAAGAGACCUUUAGAGUGUACAUGAAGCGAAACCUGACAGAAAUGAGAAAAAAUGUCACAAGUAGAGUUGGAAAUGUUAACAGUCCCCCUCAGUAAUAUCAGUAAUAGGAAAAUCUGGAAAAUUCCCAAAUAUUUGGUAGCAUAUCUAAAUAAGGCUUCCAUCAAAGAAGAAAUUAUAAGGAAAAUUAGGAACUAUUUUCAAUGGAGUGAAUAUGCAAUAUAUCCCACAAUUAUUUGUGGGAUACAUUAUGAUAUGUAUAUUGUGGGAUAUAUUGUGCAGUUAAAGCACCACUUACAGGAAUUAUGUACAGUUGGCCCUUGAACAAUGUGGGGGUUAGGAGUGCUGACUCUCCCCUGAGCAAAAAUUCACAUAUAACUAUGGAGUCUCCAAAAGCUUAACUGCCCAUAUCCUACUAUUAACUGGAAGCCUUACCAAUAAUAGUCAGUUAACACAGAUCUUGUAUGUUAUGUGUAUUAUAUACUGUACUGUUAGAAUAAAGUAGGCUAUAAAGACAAAUGAAAAUGUUACUAAGAAAAUCAUAAGGAAGAGAAAAUAUUUUUACUACUCACUAAGUGGAAGUGGAUCAUCACAAGGGUUUUCAUCCGCAUCAUCUUCCUGUUGUCUAGGCAGAGCAGGAGGAAGAGGGGUCAGUCUUGCUGUGUCAGGGGCGGCAGAUGUGGAAGAAAACCCUGUACGAGUGGGCCUGUGCAGCUCAAACUCAUGUUGCUCAAGGGUCAACUGUACUUUUUAAUGCUUAUAGCAGAAGCGAAGAAAGGUAUGAAAUCAGUGAUCUAAUCUUUUAAGAAGCUAUAAAUUGGCCCAGUGAGGGGGCUCAUGCUGGUAAUUCCAGCACUUGGCGGGCAAAGACAGGAGGAUCGCUUGAGGCCAGGAGUUAGAGACCAGCCUGGGAACAUACAAGACUCCCCUCUCUACAAAAAAAAAAAAAAAAAAAAUUAAAAGAAGCUGUAAAUAAAAACUAAAAUAACUAGAAGGAAGGAAAGAAAAAAGAUACAAAUUGCCAGUAUUAGGAAUGAAAUAGGACAUCACUAACAGAUGCUACAUACAUUCAAAGGAGGCUAAGGGAAUAAUGUGGACAACUUCAAGCCAAUAAAUUUGACAAUUUAAAUGGAAGAGACAAAUUCCCUGGAAGACACAAAUUACCAAAACUGAUUCAAAAAGAAAUGGAGGCUGGGCGCAGUGGCUCACGCCUGUAAUCCCAACACUUUAGGAGGCUGAGGCAGGCGGAUCACGAGGUCAAGAGAUCGAGACCAUCCUGGCCAACUUGGUGACACCCCAUCUCUACUAAAAAUACAAAAAUUAGCUGGGAGUGGUGGUGGGCACCUAUAAUCCCAGGUACUCGGGAGGCUGCGGCAGAAGAAUCACUUGAACCCGGGAGGCGGAAGUUGCAGUGAGCCGAGAUCACGCCACUGCACUCAAGCCUGGCGACAAAGUGAGACUCUGUCUCAAAAAAAAAAAAAAAAAAGACAAAAAGAAAUAGAAACUCUGAAUAACCCACAAUUUAUUGAAGAAUAUAAUAAUAAUCUAAAACCUUCCCGGCUGGGCGCGGUGGCUCACGCCUGUAGUCCCAGCACUUUGGGAGGCCGAGGCGGGCGGAUCACGAGGUCAGGAGAUCGAGACCAUCCUGGCUAACACAGUGAAACCCCGUCUCUACUAAAAAUACAAAAAAUUAGCCGGGCGCGGUGGUGGGCGCCUGUAGUCCCAGCUACUCAGGAGGCUGAGGCAGGAGAAGGGCGUGAACCUGGGAGGCGGAGCUUGCAGUGAGCCGAGAUUGUGCCACUGCACUCCAGCCUCAGAGACAGAGCAAGACUCCAUCUCAAAAAAAAAGAAAAGAAAAGAAAACCUUCCCACAGAACUCCAGACUCAGAUCAUUUCACUGGUGAUUUUUUUUUUUUUUUUUUUGAGGUGGAGUCUUCCUCUGUUGUUCAGGCUGGAGUGCAGUGGUGCCAUCUCAGCUCACUGCACCCUCCGCCUCCCAGAUUCAAGCAAUUCUCCUCCCUCAGCCUCCCGAGUACCUGGAAUUACAGGCGUGCACCACCACGCCCAGCUAAUGUUUGUAUUUUUAGUAGAGACAGGGCUUCACCAUGUUGGCCAGGCUGGUCUCAACCUGCUAAGUUCAGGUGAUCCGCCUGCCUCUGUCUCCCAAAGUGCUGGGAUUACAGGCAUGAGCCACUGUGUCUGGCCUCACUGGUAAAUUCUAUAAAACAUGUAAGGAAGAGAUAAUACCAAUCUUAACCAUACUCUUUCAAAAAACGGAGAAGGGAACACUUCAACUCAUCCUAGGAGGAGACUAGCACAAUUCUAAUACCAAACCAGAGGAAAAAAAAACUUCAAAAUGGUGUCUCUCAUGACCCUGGACAGAAAAGUCCUUAACAAAAAUACUGGUAAAUCAGAUUCAACAAUCUGUAAUUCACAAAGAUAACAUCAGUAUAUGUUCUCCUGACAGUGGGUCCUUAGUAUAAUCAUUGUCUACUUCAUUUCUUUGCAAUGCUAUUAUUAAGGCUUGAUGGAAUAUUUAUUUUUUAAACAGCUUAAUUAAGGUAUAAUGACAUGCAAUAUACUGCUCAUAUUUAAAGUGUACAAUAUGAUAAGUUUUGACAUACACAUAUAUUCAAUGAAACCAUUGCCACAAUCAAGAUAAUAAACAGAUCCAUCACCCACAAAA